CUGCGCGGAUCGGCGUCCGCAGCGGGCGGCUGCUGAGGUGAGGGCCGGGCCAGAGGAGAGGCAUACCCACUGGGGCGUAGGUCUGGGACUCCCCCUGUCCGCCCUGGCGCGACCUCAGGACUCUCCGUGUCCCCUCCGUGACCCCCGCGGCCCGGGCCGCUCUUUGCAUCUUGUCUUGCCCACAGCUGGCCUCGGCCAGGUCCGAGGGCCUGGAUGCGACCUUGGGGCAGCCCCUACUCUUCCGGGCAGCCCACUUCCGCGGCCACCGGUGCAGGGCAUGCCCCGGGGCCGUGGAGCUGCCUUGAGGUGCAGUGUUGGGGAUCCAGAGCCAUGUCGGACCUGCUACUACUGGGCCUGAUUGGGGGCCUGACUCUCUUACUGCUGCUGACGCUGCUGGCCUUUGCCGGGUACUCAGGGCUACUGGCUGGGGUGGAAGUGAGUGCUGGGUCACCCCCCAUCCGCAACGUCACUGUGGCCUACAAGUUCCACAUGGGGCUCUAUGGUGAGACUGGGCGGCUUUUCACUGAGAGCUGCAGCAUCUCUCCCAAGCUCCGCUCCAUCGCUGUCUACUAUGACAACCCCCACAUGGUGCCCCCUGAUAAGUGCCGAUGUGCCGUGGGCAGCAUCCUGAGUGAAGGUGAGGAAUCGCCCUCCCCUGAGCUCAUCGACCUCUACCAGAAAUUUGGCUUCAAGGUGUUCUCCUUCCCGGCACCCAGCCAUGUGGUGACAGCCACCUUCCCCUACACCACCAUUCUGUCCAUCUGGCUGGCUACCCGCCGUGUCCAUCCUGCCUUGGACACCUACAUCAAGAUGCCCAAGAUCUUUUGGAAGCCGGAGCAUAUCCCAAGAGCAUGGAGAACUUGUUCAUAAAUCUGAUCUGGUUAGUUUGGCUCUGGCUUUGACCAAAGACAUCCAUAGUGCUUAUCCCACACUCCUGGCUCAGAUGAAUGGACAGGCCACUUUAUUCUCAUCCUGCUGGAGGCCUGCAAAGCAAGGACCUGAGGCUCCCAGUGUCUGGGCAGGCCCCAGGUAAUCAUGUAUUGCCCGUGGCCCUGCCUGUGCAUGGGCUUAUACAUCUGCUCCCAGAGGCCAGGGCUGGGACAGCAGUGGCAGGCUCUGUUUCCUUUACUUCCUGACUUGGUUACUGGCAAUGCUGGCAGCCCAACCUUCCUGGAGGAAGGAGAGCCAGUCACCUGGUCAUCUGACGGGUUUCUGUGUCUACAGAAAUUUUUUUAAAACUUGCCCUGUUACACAUCCCUCCUCCCCUAAACGUUUUGUAAACUUGGUUGCUAGGGAAAUGACCCCAGUUUGGGCUUGGACGUGAUUGUUCAUUCAUUUAACUUGUAUUUAUAGUCUGUGUGCCAGGUGCUAUAAUGGGCACAAUGUGAAUGAAACGUUGGUGCAUGAAACAGCCAUUCACAGUGAGGUGGUGAAGAUAGGUAAUAAAUAUCAGACAAAAAUAGGACGUGUGCUAGAGAAGGAGAGGGUGAGAAAAGUCAGGGAACCAACUUGGACAGAAUGGUCAGGGACAGCCUCUCAGAGGAGAUAACCUCAAGGCAGAGUCCUAGAAGAGCCUUUAGAGAGGAGAUAAGAACUUCUAGUCAGAGCUUUGGUCUAAAUGCAGCAGGAAGUCACUGCAGUGUUCCAACCAGGAAAAUAACACAGUUGGAGCCACGUCUGUACAAGAUGAGCUGUCCCAUCUCUGGGCAGGGUGGGACUGGACCACAGAUCUGGGACCAGGUGGAGAUGCUUAGGCCUGGGGCUAAGGAAUUAGCCUAGGAGGCUGUCAUGAAUCCCAUUGUGAGUGGUGGCAGCUUGGGCAGGCCCAGCGGCUAUAGAGCUGUGGACAAGGAUGGAGAUUUACAAUCACUUUUGGGAUAGAACUGAUAGACUUUGGGUGGAUUCACUGUUGUGGAAGGAGAGGCAGUGAGGGAGUCACAGAGGGCUCUGCUCCCCUCUGGCCUGGGCAGGUGGGCAAGUAUGUAGUGAUGCUUUCACUGACAUGUGGGGAACUGAGGGAGGCCCUGGUUUUGGGGGGAAGGUAGCUAUUUGGGCUAUGUCAGGGGAGCUGCCUGAGAUACAUCUAAGUUGGGGGGUGUGGAGUCAGCAAUGGUAUGUGUGGCCUGGAGUUGAGGAAAGGCUGGGCUGGUGGAUAUAUUUGGGGACAUCAGCCUGUUGGCAGUAUUUGACCUGGGAGGCUGCCCUGUGCCUCCCUGCCUCUGUGGGACCAGGUAGGCAGUGGACAGCCUGUGGCAGCAAAGGCUGCGCAGAGGGCGUGGCCAGUGUGGCAGGGGUCAGGGAACAGGACGAGAGUCAGUGGGAGUGAGAGCCUGGUACACUUGGAGGAUCCUUGCAACUUUGUUCACCAAAGCAGCUUGGGGAAAGGGACACAGCGUUGAUGAUGGAAAUGGGAGUUCAGAUGUCCCUGGAGUCUGGUGUUGGGGCUGAGGAAUGAAUAAAUGAGGCCCUGGGUCACCAGCUGUGUCCUUGGCGGUCAAAGACAGGUUUGAAGAAUCAGGAGUGAGAAGACCUGGAAAGGGGAGGGCUGUCACGGUGAUAAGGCAAGGGCACAGGGAGAAUAGAGGGGAGUUUCCUUUGUGAGCUGGAGGGUGGUGGCCAAAAGGGGUGUGGGGCAGGAUGUGCUUGCCUGGCUGCGGUUGGACUGGAGGUGGGGGCGGGCUGGCUGGUGGUGUGGGCAGGAAGGAAGAUACCAGUGCCCUAGGCCUGCUUAGUGUGCUGCCUCUGGGGAGUCCCGCCCCAUUUCAUUCAAGGAAGGCCUCUCCAGUCCUGUCGGUGCCAUCCUCAACCUCAUGGGCCCAUCUGGAGGGGCACCCCUGGGAAAGAGACUUCUUGGGUUCCAGACCUCAGAACAGGACAUGUGGCAUGUGGUGUGGUGGUGAGCAACUCAGCCACCAAAGCCUUUUCCUGGCUUCAGGGGUUUAUUUUUAGACACCUUUGUCCAAAUUUCCCGGCCCCUGACAGCUUCACAAGUUGCCUGGUUUUGACGUCACCUCUUUGAUGAAAGCCCUUCCUCCUUCCUCCCCGCUCCCAUGGGAGCCUGUCAGCUGUGCUCCUGGAGUGGGGGUUGAGACAAGGAAGCCAGUGAUAUGGGGGAGAGCAAGGGGCUUCUCCCAGAGACAGGUGUGAGGCAUGCUUGUGUGGGCUUGGCCAUCAGCGGGGAGAGUAAGAUAGAGGCCGGCUGCCCACAGAAGAGGCAUGGCCGAAGGUCCUGGGCUUGUUUUGGCAGCAGGGUGUGGGGGUUGCCUCUGCCCCUGUGUUUAGCCUGACCUUGCGUCUUGGGGAACAAAGCCAGGGGAGAGAUGAGGAAGGGGCUAGCUCUGUUUGCUGGUCACAGCCUGCAGUGGACAGGGGUGGCCCUGUGCCUCUCUCAGCCCAGGAGACAGCAAGGAGAGAGUAUAAGGCUCCCUUCCAUCCCUGCCUUCAUCUCCCCUGCCCUGAGGUCAGAGAAAGGAGAUUACUAAUGAGACUAGUUGCGUCUCACUCUUCUAGCACCGACAGCUUUUAACUGUGUGUGCGUGCGCGUGUGUACACCCUUCUUUUUCUCUCUGGAUCUGGGACUGCUGUGAAGGCUCUUCAAAUGGAAUGACAGCAGCCGUCAGCUUUCUGCUUUGGCAGGGGUGAGAGAGGCCAGGAGCCCUGCUGCCAGGAGUUGCGGGGGGAGGACUUGGCAGGCUCACCAGCCUCUCCAGAGGCUAGGUGAGGGGCAGGGGUGAAUGGAUCUUAGCUUCGGGUUUGGGAGGUGGAGAGCAGCUGCUGUCCCGGGAGUUGCAGAUGUGCCUGAGCCUGGAACAGGAUUGGUCUCAUGGGACAGAGGGACCUGAAGUUCACGGCGAGAGGCCCAAGGAGAAGCACUUGUCAGGACUCUCGGGAUUCUGGAAGGGAUGGCUGAUCUCAGCUUUCCUGGUUUGCAUGGCAGCCUCUGGCUCUCUGGCUAGCCUUCCCCAGCUUGGCAGCCUGGCAAACUGCUAUAGAUGCUGGAACUCUGCCUUUCUCCAUAUAAACUGCUAAGGGCCCCCAGGCUGAACACUCAUUCCCCUGGAAUCCAUGCGUACUGUGUGACCAUCACUCCAUAUGGAAGAUGCCUCAGCUUUGUCAGGCUGCUCCGCUGGAGUCCAAGGAGGUGGCCUCUAGUACAGGAGGAGACCACUCCCCAAGUCCCAGGAAAGGGGUAUCUUCUGGAAGCUGCAGGAUGGAACAGAGCUUGCUUGAAAUUGCAAACCUGCAGAGGGGAGAUGGGGCCCAGAUGUGAGCCCAGAGCAAUGGGCAGAGGCCCCCAAAUUCACCAGUCUUAAUGAGUGUCCAGGGAAGGCUUCGGACACAUGGAACAGACCAGGACUGAGGGAUGGGCCUGGGAAUUCGAUGUGUGGGAUUGUGUGUGUAAGGUCUCUAGUGCAGUUUGCUCAUAUCUGUCUGUAGCACUUGGUGAGGAAGGCCAUUGAGAGUGUUUGACACACAGCCAAGCCCCCAUGCCUGAUUUCUCUCCCAGACCCGUCCAGAAUCUUUUUCAAAAGUGCCCUUCCCCAUGGUCUCUGAUUUCAGGGAGUUUUUAGGGGGAGGGUCUUUGUAAAAUGGUUUGAGCCUCCUCUCCCAAGUUUAGGGUGUUACAGGGCAUUGUUCAUGUAGUGGCUGAUUGGCUGGGGAGUGCAGGUGGCCCUGGAGGUCAGACUAAUGUCUGACUAUCCACCAUCAAAUUGGAGAAAAGCGUGUAAGUAAGGAGGGGUCACCGAAUAUAGUGAGCCUGUGAGGGGAACCUUGGUGGCCGAAUUCUGGGACAGCUGGGUUGACUGGGACUGUCUUACCAGGGGCUUAAAGGGGAUAAGGCCAGGUGUGGUGGCUCAUGCCUGUAAUCCCAACACUUUGGGAGCCUGAGGUGGGAGGAUCACUUGAGCCCAGGAGUUCCAGACCAGCCUGGGCAACAUAAGUGAGAUCCUGCCUCUAAAAAAAACAGAAAAAAAAUUAGCCAGGCAUUUGUAGUCCCAGCUACUCAGGAGGCUGAGGUGGGAGGAUCGCUUGAGCCUGGGAGGUCAAGGCUGCAGUGAGCCAUGAUUGUGCCACUGCAGUCUAUCCUGGGUGACAGAGUGAGACUCUGUCUCAAAAAUAAAUAAAUAGAUAAAUGAAGGGGGCAUGGUGGCUCACACCUGUAAUCCCAGCACUUUGGGAGGCUGAGGCAGGUAGAUUACUCCAGCUCAGGAGUUUGAGACCAGCCUGGACAACAUGGUGAAACCUCGUCUCUACAGAAAAAAAAUACAAAAAAAUUAGCUGGGCGUGGUGGCGUGCACCUGUGGUCUCAGCUACUCGGGAGGCUGAGACAGGAGAAUUGCUUGAGCUCAGGAGACAGAGGUUGCAGUGAGCCAAGAUCACGCCAUUGCACAUUAGCUUGGGUAACAGGAGUGAAACCCAUCUCAAAAAAAUAAAAGUAAAAACAUUAAAAAAAAAAAAAAAGGGAAGGAAGG